AGCACUUCCCAGAAGAGAAAACUCCUCCAAAAGCAGCUCUCACUAUCAGAAAACCCAACUACAGUUGUGAACGCCUUCAUUUUCUGCCUGAGGUCUCAGUCCGUCGGCCCAGACUGAAGUGCAGUGGCACAAUCAUAGCUCGCUGCAGCCUCGACCUUCCAGGCUUAAACGAUUCUCCCACCUCAGCCUCUCGAGUUGCUGGGACCACAGGUCACUGUGCAUGGCAUCAUCCUGGCCCCCUCUAGAGCUCCAAUCCUCCAACCAGAGCCAGCUCUUCCCUCAAAAUGCUACGGCCUGUGACAAUGCUCCAGAAGCCUGGGACCUGCUGCACAGAGUGCUGCCAACAUUUAUCAUCUCCAUCUGUUUCUUCGGCCUCCUAGGGAACCUUUUUGUCCUGUUGGUCUUCCUCCUGCCCCGGCGGCAACUGAACGUGGCAGAAAUCUACCUGGCCAACCUGGCAGCCUCUGAUCUGGUGUUUGUCUUGGGCUUGCCCUUCUGGGCAGAGAAUAUCUGGAACCAGUUUAACUGGCCUUUCGGAGCCCUCCUCUGCCGUGUCAUCAACGGGGUCAUCAAGGCCAAUUUGUUCAUCAGCAUCUUCCUGGUGGUGGCCAUCAGCCAGGACCGCUACCGCGUGCUGGUGCACCCUAUGGCCAGCCGGAGGCAGCAGCGGCGGAGGCAGGCCCGGGUCACCUGCGUGCUCAUCUGGGUUGUGGGGGGCCUCUUGAGCAUCCCCACAUUCCUGCUGCGAUCCAUCCAAGCCGUCCCAGAUCUGAACAUCACCGCCUGCAUCCUGCUCCUCCCCCAUGAGGCCUGGCACUUUGCAAGGAUUGUGGAGUUAAAUAUUCUGGGUUUCCUCCUACCACUGGCUGCGAUCGUCUUCUUCAACUACCACAUCCUGGCCUCCCUGCGAACGCGGGAGGAGGUCAGCAGGACAAGGUGCGGGGGCCGCAAGGAUAGCAAGACCACAGCGCUGAUCCUCACGCUCGUGGUUGCCUUCCUGGUCUGCUGGGCCCCUUACCACUUCUUUGCCUUCCUGGAAUUCUUAUUCCAGGUGCAAGCAGUCCGAGGCUGCUUUUGGGAGGACUUCAUUGACCUGGGCCUGCAAUUGGCCAACUUCUUUGCCUUCACUAACAGCUCCCUGAAUCCAGUAAUUUAUGUCUUUGUGGGCCGGCUCUUCAGGACCAAGGUCUGGGAACUUUAUAAACAAUGCACCCCUAAAAGUCUUGCUCCAAUAUCUUCAUCCCAUAGGAAAGAAAUCUUCCAACUUUUCUGGCGGAAUUAAAACAGCAUUGAACCAAGAA